AGUCGGCGCGCGGGCCGGGCCGGGCCGGCGCCCCUCUGCCUCGCGCGCUUGUCGCGUUGCCCCGGGCUCCGGGGGAUGCCCCCGGCCGAGCCCUUCUCAUGGCCGCCGACGUCUUCAUGUGCUCCCCGCGCCGGCCUCGCAGCCGGGGCCGCCAGGUGCUGCUCAAGCCCCAGGUGUCCGAGGACGACGACGACUCGGACACGGAUGAGCCGUCCCCGCCGCCCGCCUCCGGCGCGGCCACCCCGGCCCGGGCCCACGCGAGCGCCGCGCCACCGCCGCCUCGGGCCGGGCCGGGCCGCGAGGAACCUCCGCGCCGCCAGCAGAUCAUCCACAGCGGCCACUUCAUGGUGUCGUCGCCGCACCGAGAGCACCCGCCCAAGAAGGGCUACGAUUUCGACACGGUCAACAAACAGACGUGCCAGACCUACAGCUUCGGCAAGACUAGCUCCUGCCACCUGUCCAUCGACGCCUCGCUCACCAAGCUCUUCGAGUGCAUGACUUUGGCCUACAGUGGGAAGUUGGUGUCUCCAAAGUGGAAGAAUUUCAAGGGCCUGAAGCUACAGUGGAGAGACAAGAUCCGGCUCAAUAAUGCCAUCUGGCGGGCCUGGUACAUGCAGUAUCUGGAGAAGCGCAAGAAUCCUGUGUGCCACUUUGUGACACCCCUGGACGGCUCUGUGGACGUAGACGAGCACCGCCGGCCGGAGGCCAUCACCACGGAAGGGAAGUACUGGAAGAGCCGCAUCGAGAUUGUGAUCCGGGAGUAUCACAAGUGGAGAACCUACUUCAAGAAAAGGCUACAGCAGCACAAGGAUGAGGACCUCUCCAGCCUGGUCCAGGACGAUGACAUGCUGUAUUGGCACAAGCACGGGGAUGGAUGGAAGACCCCCGUCCCCAUGGAGGAGGAUCCCCUGCUGGACACAGACAUGCUCAUGUCGGAAUUCAGCGACACCCUCUUCUCCACACUUUCUUCACACCAGCCGGUGGCCUGGCCCAAUCCCCGGGAAAUAGCACAUCUGGGAAAUGCAGACAUGAUCCAGCCGGGACUGAUUCCUUUGCAGCCUAACCUGGACUUCAUGGACACCUUUGAGCCUUUCCAGGACCUCUUCUCUUCUAGCCGCUCCAUUUUUGGCUCCAUGCUACCUGCAUCUGCCUCAGCACCUGUACCAGAUCCCAACAACCCACCUGCACAGGAGAGCAUCCUGCCGACCACAGCCCUCCCCACUGUGAGCCUUCCUGACAGCCUCAUCGCGCCCCCUACCGCCCCAUCCCUGGCUCACAUGGAUGAGCAGGGCUGUGAACACACCUCCCGGACUGAGGACCCGUUUAUCCAGCCCACGGACUUCGGUCCCUCAGAGCCGCCACUGAGUGUCCCGCAGCCCUUCCUCCCUGUCUUCACCAUGCCCCUGCUGUCUCCCAGCCCCGCCCCACCGCCCAUCUCCCCCGUGUUACCAUUAGUUCCUCCUCCUGCCACUGCCCUGAACCCCCCGGCUCCACCCACCUUCCAUCAGCCACAGAAGUUUGCUGGAGUCAACAAAGCGCCGUCUGUCAUCACCCACACGGCCUCUGCCACCCUCACCCACGAUGCCCCCGCCACCACCUUUAGCCAGAGUCAGGGCCUUGUGAUCACCACCCAUCACCCUGCCCCGUCAGCGGCCCCUUGUGGGCUGGCACUGUCUCCUGUCACCCGGCCUCCCCAGCCACGGUUAACUUUUGUGCACCCCAAACCUGUAUCCUUGACUGGGGGCAGGCCUAAGCAGCCCCACAAAAUAGUGCCUGCUCCCAAACCAGAGCCCGUGUCCUUGGUGUUGAAGAAUGCCCGUAUCGCCCCAGCUGCCUUUUCAGGCCAACCACAAGCGGUGAUCAUGACGUCAGGGCCUCUGAAGAGAGAAGGGAUGUUGGCCUCCACCGUGUCCCAGUCCAACGUGGUCAUUGCGCCUGCUGCCAUCGCCAGGGCUCCUGGGGUCCCGGAGUUCCACAGCAGCAUCCUGGUGACAGAUCUCGGCCAUGGCACGAGCAGCCCGCCUGCCCCCGUCUCCCGGCUCUUCCCAAGCACAGCGCAAGACCCCCUGGGGAAGGGCGAGCAGGUCCCGCUGCAUGGGGGCAGCCCCCAGGUCACUGUCACAGGGCCCAGUCGGGACUGCCCAAACUCAGGGCAGGCCUCUCCGUGUGCAUCGGAGCAGAGCCCCAGUCCUCAAUCUCCCCAGAACAACUGCUCAGGGAAAUCCGACCCCAAAAAUGUGGCUGCACUAAAGAACCGGCAGAUGAAGCACAUCUCAGCUGAGCAGAAAAGGCGCUUCAACAUCAAGAUGUGCUUCGACAUGCUCAACAGCCUCAUCUCCAACAAUUCCAAGCUGACCAGUCACGCCAUCACACUGCAGAAGACUGUGGAGUACAUCACCAAGCUGCAGCAGGAGAGAGGCCAGAUGCAGGAGGAGGCCCGGCGGCUGCGGGAGGAGAUCGAGGAGCUCAAUGCCACCAUCAUCUCCUGCCAGCAGCUGCUCCCUGCCACGGGAGUCCCCGUUACCCGGCGCCAGUUUGAUCACAUGAAAGACAUGUUUGACGAAUACGUGAAAACCCGGACCUUGCAGAAUUGGAAGUUCUGGAUUUUCAGCAUCAUCAUCAAGCCGCUGUUUGAGUCGUUCAAGGGCAUGGUGUCCACCAGCAGCCUGGAGGAGCUGCACCGGACGGCGCUCUCCUGGCUGGACCAGCACUGCUCCCUGCCCAUCCUCAGGCCGAUGGUAUUGAGCACGCUGCGGCAGCUGAGCACCUCCACCUCCAUCCUCACAGACCCGGCACAGCUGCCAGAGCAGGCGUCCAAGGCUGUCACCAGGAUUGGCAAGAGAUUGGGAGAGUCCUAGCUGCUUAGCUGGCAUGUGGCCGCAUGAGAUGCCAGGAGACCCUUCCCUGCCCAUGGAGAGUAGGCUGCGCCCCCCAGCCCUUCCUGACGCUCAGCCUCGGGGCCUCUCUCCAACUCUGCCGGCCCACCGUGGCAUCGGGAGGCCAUGCUCAGGUCUGAAGCAGGUUUGGGGCCUGCUGACAGCAAUAGCCCGCCUUUGGGAACCCCUUGCUGUGAACUCUCUCACUCAGUGACCUCAGUCACCAACCUCCUCUGCCCUCGGGGCAGCCCACACAAAAGGGAAGUGCUGGCCGUGCUGGUCCUGCCCUGCUGGUGGCCUGCCGGGCCUGGCGCCGGUGAGCGGAAUCGAUGGGAUGAGGGUGACAGGGCCUGCUCCUGUCCUGAGGCCCAGCCUUGUCCCUCCUGCCACGUCCUGUCCACAUGCAUGCCUCUGCCUGAUGCCCUGCUCCACUCUCUGGUCUGCCCGUGGGGCAGUUGGAAGGCGUCUUUCUUUCUCCCCUCAACUCUGACAGCACCCAGCCCUUGUGGAUGGACUUGGGCUUCUAUUCAGGCUUAUGCAUGGCAGGCUGCCAGGGGGAAGUGCCUUCUUCAGAGGUCCUCCAGGACACAUGUGUGCAGAAACGGUGGAUGUGGAACACACAGGACCAGAAUGGAAGCGUGUGAUGCACGGUGGCUGCUCUGGCUGAGAGGCCCUGCUGGGCAUGUUUCAUCUGUCCCCUUUUAGCUCCACCUGACAUUGCAGGAUCCAUGGGGACUCAGCCCAGGGCCUUCUCGGAUGUCACCUCACCGCUGUGGCCCUUCUGCCGUUCUUCUCCACUUGGCUCCAGCUGCAGCUGUUGACAGAUCAAGCAUGUCCUGUGGGAGCUUAGAACCCUGAAGUUCUAGUGUCUGAAAGAUCAGACUCCACGUCCUGCUGUCAGCCUUGUCAUCUUGUCUGAUGUCUUUCAGCUGGGAGCCCCAAACCAGGACAGUUCUCGGACCAAAGAUGCCCCCACACUCAAAAGUCUGUCCCGUCUUGUGUUUGGAGAAGGAAACAAUGUUGGCAGGCAGCACUCUGUGGUGGUCAGCCCUCAGAGCUGUUUCUAGGCAUCUCUCAGAUCAGACAGCAAAGAAUCUACCCAGAUCUGGGCUGGGUGGAGGUGUGGCUGGGCUGGGGGCCAUUCUGAGCCUGCAGUGAGAGUUUGGCCCAGCCUCAGUCCUUGCUCUUCUCUGGCUACCUCUGCAGGGAGCUGCAGGGGCAAGCACUCUCUCCAGCACUCAGGAAGCCCGGCCGAGGGUACCUCCUCGUGGAAAGAAUGCACUUUAAAGCUCUGCUGAGGAGUUCGGAGCCCAGGCUUUCAGGCGACCUCUGCCCUCCCUGCCUCUCCUCACCCUCCCUCUCUUCCUGCAGGGCCUGGGAAGGGCUUUGAGGGAGCCUGGGAGCCAUGUGAAGAGGGGCACGCCUGGGCUGUCCCACAGUUUAGAUCCAGUUGGAGGUUCUCCCUGGCUCCUGCAGGCCUGCGGGGAUCUCUCCCCACUUCAGGCCUCCGGCCAGCUGCCUGCCCUCUUGUCUGUGCUUCAGCCCUGCACAAAAGCAGCUUGGUGACACCACUCAGCCACCCAGAGUACGUGUUUACAGGCUUUCCAGAUCACCUUCCUGUGGGGUGAACGUAAUGAGGCGGGGCUGGUCCUUGGAAUUUCCCCUGGAAAAUGGUAACAGACUCCAUCCUUGACCCGGGGAUGAGCAUGAAGGCAUUGUCCCAAAGGCAGAGGCCACCGUGGUAGGAAUUCCACCAAGGCCAGAAGGGAAAAAGGAAGAACCCACCGUGUCUGGCUGUGCGGGCCCUGGGGAGGGUCGUGAGUGCAGCCCCUCUCUACUUCUGUGCCUUUGUAAAACGUGUAGAUAACCGCAGUGGUUGGCUGAGCCAAGAACUCUCCUAAAUCAGUGGCUUUCUCCCCACCCCUUGCUGGGGAGUCAUUUUUAAAAAAAUCUGUGGGAUAUAAAAUUGGCCUCCUGCUGCUUCAGCCUACCUCUCCCUCUGCUGACUUAAUGUCGUGAUUCUGUUUCUUCAGAUAUUUAAGGCUGUUAGGUUGUGUGAGCCUUGAAGUGUGUGUGUGUGUCCCAGCGACUGUCCACUGUCCAGGAGAUGCAUGUCUUUGUAUUGGAGAUAUUUCUGUAACUCAUUCUCUUGGUGCUCACGAUUGCCAUGGCCAUAGGGCCACAGUGCCGUAUCUGCUGCAGACAUGAUUGUUUCUUGUUCUAGAGGUUUUCUUGUUUUCGAAUCUUGCCUGAUGAAUCCAGCCAGACCAAGGGGCCUAGAUUUGACCUCUGUCCUGGGCUCCUGGGCCAGGUGCAGGAACAUCUGAGGCCACUCUGCUGGCCACCUCCAGUGGGUGCUGACCACAGGAUGGGCUUUGUUUACACUCAUUUUCACCCUGAUUCUUGCCCCCACUUUCAUAAAAGAAACUUCAAAAUGCUGACGCUUUGGAGAGUAAGAAAAUCAAUCUUGGCUGGGCACGGUGGCUCCUGCCUGUGAUCCUAGCACUUUGGGAGGCUGAAGCUGAAGGAUCACUUGAGCUCAGGAGUUGGAGACCAACCCUGGCAACAUAACAAGACCCUGUCUCUACAAAAAAAAAAAAAAAAAAAAAAAAUUUAGCCGUGUGUAGCAGUGAGUGCCUGUGGUCCCAGCUACUUGGGCCUGAGGCUGGAGGAUUGCUUGAGCCUAGAAGUUGCAGUGAGCUAUGAUCAUGCCACACUGUACUCCAGCCUGGAUGACAGAGUGAAACCCUGCCUCUAAAUAAAAGAAAAUAGAGGCAGACUGUGGUGGCUCACGCCUGUAAUCCCAGCACUUUGGUAGGCCAAGGCGGGUGGAUCACCUGCAGUCAGGAGUUCACAACCAGCCUGACCAACAUGGUGAAACCCUGUCUAUACUAAAAAUACAAAACAUUAGCCACGUGUGGUGGUACACGCCUGUAAUCCCAGCUACUCGGGAGGCUGAGUCAGGAGAAUCACUUGAACCUGGGAGGCGGAGGUUGCAGUGAGCUGAGAUUGUACCACUGCACUCCAGCCUGGGUGACAGAGCAAAACCCUAUCUCAAAAAAAAAAAGAAGAAAAAAAUAGAAAAUCCAAAAAGAAAAACCAGAAGGCCUGCUGGCGUAUAAAUCCCUGGGCGGGUUUCUGAUAAAUUGCCCUGUGCUGUCAGCCCCUGCACUGCACUGCUGCCUUCCAUGGUGGGUGGGAGACCCCAGAGCGGGGCAGGCGCCACUGAGGGCUUUUCUUGGAGUCGGCCAGCAGGCCACGCAGCAUCCGGCACCCUGGGCGGGCUGGCUAGCUGCCUUCUUAGGACAUCUCUACUUUGAAGGAUUUUACCGCAGGAAGCAAUAGCAGCGCUGGCCAUUGGUGCUGAUGACAGCAUUGGGUCUGGUUGAGGGGAAGGGGCUGGAAAGCAGCAGACCCCCCCAGUGCUGCGCAUGGUCCCGGAGCUGUCAGCCAGGGGAGUGGGGUCAGCCGUCAGCCAGCCCUCCCAUUUCCCGCCCAUGGGCCCUGACCACACUCCCUUUUCUAGAAGUCAAUCCUAAGGUUUCUCUGCUCUGGCUAAGAGGAUGUAAAUUUGGAUUCUUAGAGGGCAUGGCACCCCCAGUCCCUGCCCAGAUAAAGUAGCACAGUGGCAGGCAGCACCUCUGUCUGUUGCUGACGUUGGGGGGCUUACACACCCACCUCAUCUCCGUGCACAGCCAUGACUGGCCCUGCCGGCAGCUGGGGUGCAGGUAAGGGUCUCUCUCAUA